AUGUGGAUGCUGGGAGAAGUAUGUGAGAUGGAAAAGUUGUUUCAUGGCAUCCAAGAAGUGAAUGAUCCUCAAGGUGUAGCAGAGGAAUUUGUAGGAGAGAGGGAUGAUUGACGUCUUCGUAUAGCCCUCCAUCCAUCCCAGUUAGCAUGGAGGGAUUUUAGGGCUACCAUUGGCUGGGUAGUGGAGUGUUGACCAAUCACAGCUCAGGGGCGUGAUUGUCUCGUCCUGGGAUCGCGAGAGGGGUAUAUACAGGGAGGCCAGGCAGCCUGGAGUUAGUCGACCGUUGCGAGACGUUGAGCUGCGGAAGAUGAGUCCAAAGCCGAGAGCCUCGGGACCUCCGGCCAAGGCCACGGAGGCAGGAAAGAGGAAGUCCUCCUCUCAGCCGAGCCCCAGUGACCCGAAGAAGAAGACUACCAAGGUGGCCAAGAAGGGAAAAGCAGUUCGUAGAGGGAGACGCGGGAAGAAAGGGGCUGCGACAAAGAUGGCGGCCGUGACGGCACCUGAGGCGGAGAGCGCGCCAGCGGCACCCGGCCCCAGCGACCAGCCCAGCCAGGAGCUCCCUCAGCACGAGCUGCCGCCGGAGGAGCCAGUGAGCGAGGGGACCCAGCACGACCCCCUGAGUCAGGAGAGCGAGGUGGAAGAACCACUGAGUCAGGAGAGCGAGGUGGAAGAACCACUGACUGUGUGGAUGGCCAGCUUUUCCCCUGUCUCCGAGAGCACCGACUAAGUUCAGGCCCAGCCGCCAGACCUCAGAGAUCUCACCAGCGGGGUGCUUGCCAUUCUGAAGAUAAUAAAAUGAAUGUGUUGCAAAUUGA